AGUGACGCGCGAGCGGCUCCCGCGACUGUGGCUCCCGAAGCUGCUUCGGGCCCCAGCGGUGAGGAAGAAGACUCUCAACCAGGGUGACUUCUAGGCGUCCUCCCGGAGCUACCGGGGACACUGGCGUUAUUGCCCGCAACACUGAGAUAGGGAAUGCUCGAGAAACAGAAGCAGGAGUAUUUUAUACAGAAAUCUUGUGAAACCACUGCCCAACCAGAGCAAUGAUUGUUCAAAGAGUGGUAUUGAAUUCUCGACCUGGAAAAAAUGGUAAUCCAGUGGCAGAGAAUUUCCGAAUGGAAGAAGUCUAUUUACCAGAUAAUAUUAAUGAAGGACAAGUACAAGUUAGAACUCUUUAUCUUUCUGUGGAUCCUUACAUGCGUUGUAGAAUGAAUGAAGACACUGGCACUGAUUAUAUAACACCUUGGCAGCUAUCUCAAGUCGUUGAUGGAGGAGGUAUUGGAAUUAUAGAAGAAAGCAAACACACAAAUUUGACUAAAGGCGAUUUUGUGACUUCUUUCUAUUGGCCCUGGCAAACCAAGGUUAUUCUGGAUGGAAAUAGCCUUGAAAAGAGAUGGGUUGUCACUGUGUUGCCCCGGCUGGUCUCAAACUCCUAGGCUCAAGCAAUCCUCCCACCUCAGCCUCCCAAAGUGCUGAGAUUACAGGUAGACCCACAACUUGUGGAUGGACACCUUUCAUAUUUUCUUGGAGCUAUAGGUAUGCCUGGUUUGACUUCCUUGAUUGGGAUACAGGAAAAAGGUCAUAUAACUGCUGGAUCUAAUAAGACAAUGGUUGUCAGUGGGGCCGCAGGUGCCUGUGGAUCUGUGGCUGGGCAGAUUGGCCAUUUCUUAGGUUGUUCCAGAGUGGUGGGAAUUUGUGGAACACAUGAGAAAUGCAUCCUCUUGACCUCAGAACUGGGCUUUGAUGCUGCAAUUAAUUAUAAAAAAGACAAUGUGGCAGAACAGCUCCGUGAAUCAUGCCCAGCUGGAGUGGAUGUUUAUUUUGACAAUGUUGGUGGUAACAUCAGUGAUACAGUGAUAAGUCAGAUGAAUGAGAACAGCCACAUCAUCCUGUGUGGUCAAAUUUCUCAGUACAACAAAGAUGUGCCUUAUCCUCCCCCGCUAUCCCCUGCUAUAGAGGCAAUCCAGAAAGAAAGAAACAUCACAAGGGAAAGAUUUCUGGUAUUAAAUUAUAAAGACAAAUUUGAGCCUGGCAUUCUACAGCUGAGUCAGUGGUUUAAAGAAGGAAAGCUAAAGAUUAAAGAGACGGUAAUAAAUGGGUUGGAAAACAUGGGAGCUGCAUUCCAGUCCAUGAUGACAGGAGGUAACAUUGGAAAGCAGAUAGUUUGCAUUUCAGAAGAAAUCUCUUUGUAAUUGCUGUAAAUGUCAUCAAGGCAAUCAUAGAUUUCUUUUCCAUUUUGCAUAUUUUCAAAGAUAUGUUAAAAAAUCCUUAGACUAUACAUAGCUCUUGAUUUAAAUGUGAUCAUAGGUGUUAUUUUUAGUUGCAUAGGGUAUUUGAUACAAUCAUUAAUGGAUCAUACACAAUAGGUUUUUAAAAAUUAAUAACUUUUAGUAAUUACUUUUAUUAAUUUAAAAUAGAACGCUUGAGAGGCACUUUGUAAAGAUUUGUUAAACUGGAAACGUUUUACAUGAUCUGAUACAACCAUUAAUGAAUCAUACACAAUAGGUUUUUUAAAAUUAAUAUUAAUAACUUUUAUUAAUUUAAAAUAGAAUGCUUAAAAUAAAAUAGAAUGCUUGAGAGGCACUGAGUAAAGAUUUGUUGAACUGGAAAUGUUUUACAUGAUUCUUAAACUGAAACUUGGUGUAAAAAUAGAAUUGAGAUGGCCUUUUUUUCACAUUGUAGACUGAAAAGAGACUUAAUGGUAUGAUGUGUACAUAGGGACUGGGGGCAGGAUUGGGGGUUUCGGAGCUUGUGUAACAGUUUUUGGGAUAGGAGACCAGCGGUUUUGGGUUGGGAUUAGUAUGGGAAGAUAAAUAACUUAGGUUGGUUAAGUUGACAAGAUUUACUCCAGAGGAUCAUCUCUUUGUAUUUGCCAAAUAAUUUACUGUAUAGCCUAAAAACUCCAUAUAUAUUGAGAAAAGCAUAUGUUUAUUUUAGGUUAGCAGGCACAUACUGUCAAGUUGUAAAGAUUGAGAGGGCAAACAGAUGUAAACAUCACUUGUAGGUGAUUAAAAAGAUUGACAGCCGGGCCUGAUGUCUCAAGCCUGUAAUCCUAGCACUUUGGGAGGCAGAGGCGGGCAGAUCACUUGAGGUCAGGAGUUCAAGACCAGCCUGGCCAACACGGUGAAACCCCAUCUCUCUAAAAAUACAAAAAUUAGCUGGGCGUGGUGGCACACGCCUGUAAUCCCAGCUACUCAGGAGGCUGAGGCUGGAGAAUCAUUUGAACCUGGGAGGGGGAGGUUGCCGUGAGCUGAGCUUGCACCAUUGCACUCCAGCCUGGGCGACAAGAGUGAAAUUCCAUCUCAAAAAACAAAAACAGAUUGACAACAAAGACAGUUUCAGAAAAUGACAGGACUGGGCAAAUUAACAAAUGUUUGUAAACAUGAAUGUUCAGGAACUACUGAUGUACCUCAAAAGUUUGUUUUAUUAAUUGUACUCAACCCUCGCAGAACAGUAAAACUGAAGAUUAUUGUUUCUGAAUGUUUUGGCUUAUGAUUGUCUACACACUGCCAAUAUACUUUUGUAUGCAACAUUUGUAAUAAGUAGAUUCAAACUGUGUUGGUAAUCAGCCUCCCCAGUUUUCGUGAGUGGCCCUUUUUUGUUACUUUUCCUGGACCAUUUCAUCGCCUGAGGGGGUUUCACUUUUCUCUGUAUGUUGCUAACUCCCAAAUCUCCAUCUGUAUUUCUGACCUCUUUCUUGAGCACUGGACCUUUACCUCCAAGUAAAUAUCCUCAACUCUG